AAACGGGGAACUUAGAAAGUGGCAGCCCCUCGGCUUGUCGCCGGAGCUGAGAACCAAGAGCUCGAAGGGGCCAUAUGACACUCCUCCCGGACCCCUGGACACACACAGCCCUGGAGACUGGAGCCUUGGAGCAUGGCAAGUCCAGAGCACCCUGGGAGCCCUGGCUGCAUGGGACCCAUAACCCAGUGCACGGCAAGGACCCAGCAGGAAGCACCAGCCACUGGCCCCGACCUCCCGCACCCAGGACCUGACGGGCACUUAGACACACACAGUGGCCUGAGCUCCAACUCCAGCAUGACCACGCGGGAGCUUCAGCAGUACUGGCAGAACCAGAAAUGCCGCUGGAAGCACGUCAAACUGCUCUUUGAGAUCGCUUCAGCUCGCAUCGAGGAGAGAAAAGUCUCUAAGUUUGUGAUGGGGAAAUCAAGGCCUGGAGAGAUGACUUAUCCAGGGUCACGUGGCGAGACAGGGACAGCACCAGAACCAGACCCGAGAUGUCCACGUCAAAGUGACAUGCUCUGAGAGGCAGCACACACAGAAUAACCCUGCAUCCAAAUUCCAGGAAGCUCUUAGGGGUCAUCCAGCUGGGCCUAGGGGUGCAGGGUCAGUGCUGAGGCCUGGGCAGGGCCGCUAGCCUCCCUGAGCUUUCUGGCUUCAGGCUGGGAGGCACAGUUCAGGGUGGACUGUGACCCCUUGGCCUAGAAUGCCCUUAGCUCUGCUCUCUAGUGGCUGUCCCCAUAGCUGGAACUCUGUUUUGGAGUGGCAAAACCAGUUCCACCUGCUGGUAGGGGUAGGUUGGCUCCCAACACAUCCCCAGCAGGCCUCUCUUGGGCUCAAAAGCCAAGCUGUGCCCAGCCACGUCUCCAAAUGCUUCCUGGCCCCCAUGCAGCAACUGCAUUUAGCUGCCUUCCCAGAAUUUCCUGCAUGCUCACACAGCCCUUCCCUCUGGGGCCCAACAAUGCCACAGCCUGUUCUAUCAAUCACCAGCUGUUUUCCUUUGAGCAGUCUCCUUUUACUUAUGCACAUUUACUUGAAAAAGAAACUUCCUAUUACUAUCCUAAAUGGAAACUCAGAAUCACUUGCUAUAAUUAGAAAGUAGCUACAAAAAUAAACACAAUGAAACCGAUCACUGUUAUUACACCCUAACCCGCUUUUACCUGAGACAGGCCCUGAGCCUGAGGCCGCUGGUAGACUUUUGUUAAAAGAGAGAGAGACAGAGACAGAGAAAUAAGCAUUAGAGACCUGCAAUCACCAAGCUGAGACUUCUCUUUGAUUUACUCAGAAGGACUGGAAAAUGUUGUCCUGCAAAAGGAGGUAAGUUUCUCACCACGUAGCGCUGAUCAUCCCGUGUUGCCCGUGCGUUGCUGCAGACCAUCUGGGGUCUUGCCCAAGCACCCUGGAGACUUUGCUCCCUGGUUUCCUGGUCACCAACUCGAGUGUUCAGCCCUGUGUGCUCUCCAGCUCCUAAGUCGUGGGCCUGGUUUCAGCUUUGAUUGCCCACUCUUGGCUUUCAACCCGUAGGCUCCGGCUCCUGACGCCACACCCUGAUAUCAAGACCCUCAGAUGGAGCGAGCGUUCUGGGCUGGUCGAAGCCUGAAGCCGCAGUAUGUCCUUGAGUGGGUCCCCCCCUACCCAUCUAGCUGUUGCCCCCAUGGUAAGAUCAAGAAAAUGCCCUCCCCUCCAAAAGUCCCCACGCCGAGCCCUCAUCUGUCAGCUCCCAGGCUCGGCCCCCUCACUAGCUCCAGGCUGGGAGGCACAGUUCAGGGCAGACUGUGGCCCCUCAGCAUAGCAUGGACUUAGCUCUGCUCUCUAGUGGCUGUCCCCAUAGCUAGAACUCUGUUUUGGAGCAGCAAAACUAGUUCCACCUGCUGGUAGGGCUAAGUUGACUCCCAACAUGUCCCCAGCGUGUUGGUGUUGGGAACCUUGAUCUAGCUGCUCGUUUUCUCAGUAACCAAAGAUCCCUGGCACUCCUACGAUGUCUCAGGCCUUAUCUAGAGCUGGGGAUACAGCAGUGACCAGGACAGAACUGGUCCCUGCCUCACGGAAGUGAAGUGUCAGGAGGCCACUCCCAAAGCAAAUGGAAGCUGGGACAGAAUGAUGUCCUCAGCCAGGUGGUCAGGGAAGGCUUCUCAGAGGGGGCGCUGUUCAAAGAAUCACAGAGCAUACAAAGGAGCUGGCCCUGGGAGCACAGAGAGGGGAGAAUUUUAGGCAAAGAGGUAGCAGGAGCACAGCCCUGAGGCAGGAAACUACCCCCCCACCACCCUCGGCAUCCUCAGUUCUGGUUUGCACCCAGAAAGGGGGUAGGUCCAGGACACACCCGGACUGAUGUGUCACACUGGCUGUGCCAGCUGAGAGAGUGGGCUCCAGGCACCACUAACAGAGAAGCCUUGCAAGGCAGGUCCAUGCACCGCCCGCCUCCAGUUACCACUCAUUGCAAAGGAAAUGAGCUGGGAGCCUGUGUGUGGGCCGUGCAGACCCUUUUGGUUACAAGCCACAAAAACCCAGGUUAAUCUGAUGAGGAAGGAAUUUAUUAUCUGUAAAGUCCAGGAGCAGGCUAGCUUUACACCAAGCAGGAUCCAAGGACCCACACUUGUCACCUCAUAUCUCUCUCUCUCUCCCACUUUCGCUUUCUCUGUCUCUUCUUAGUUCUGCUUUCCUCCACUGUGCCUUCGCUCUCAGAGAGAGCUCUCCCCUGGCAGUGACAAGAUGGCUGCAGCAGCUCCAGCAACCUCAGAGGACUCCCCCAUCCAGGGUCCUUGUGAGCUCCUCAUCUGUAGGAUGUGCAGUAAACACUCACGUGUCCUUUCCUGAGGAGCCCAGUGGCUGGGGUGGGGGCUGAGGGGCAGCCCCUAUGCCCUCACAGUGCAGCAACCUUGGUUAGCUCACCCAUCAGGGCAGACUUGGGCAGAAAUCAUGUCUUGGCAUAUUGUUUUGUAAUCUGCUUUUUAAAUUGUCACUAUAUAUUAUGAGCAUUUCCCUAUAAUAUACAAUAUUCUUCCACAUUAUGUUUAAUGGUUUCAUUGUAUUCUAAUGCAUAUUCUAUAGUUAUUUUAACCACCCCACAAUGUUGCAAAAUGUCCUUAUUUGGGACAACACUGCUGCAAACACUUUGACCCAUAUGUCCUUUUUGUGUGCACUCUUAUGGCAACUUCUAACGGUGGCAUUUCUGAAUCAUAGACACUUUUUUGACUUCUACAUAUUUUAUUUUUUUAGUUGACAAAAACUGUAUUUAUGAAUCAUAAACACUUAAUGAUUUUGCUAUU